AUAUAGUAACAUAGUGUGGUACUUUGUCUUGAGGAGAUGUCCUGGACUCACACGGAAACUUAGGGCUACGGAAUGAAGUUCUCACUCCCAUUAGGUGACAGGUUUUUAGAGAAGCCAAUCAGCGUCGCCGCGGUCCUGGUUCUAAAGUCCUCGCUCACCCACCCGGACUCAUUCUCCCCAGACGCCAAGGAUGGUGGUCAUGGCACCCCGAACCCUCUUCCUGCUACUCUCGGGGGCCCUGACCCUGACCGAGACCUGGGCGGGCUCCCACUCCAUGAGGUAUUUCAGCGCCGCCGUGUCCCGGCCCGGCCGCGGGGAGCCCCGCUUCAUCGCCAUGGGCUACGUGGACGACACGCAGUUCGUGCGGUUCGACAGCGACUCGGCGUGUCCGAGGAUGGAGCCGCGGGCGCCGUGGGUGGAGCAGGAGGGGCCAGAGUAUUGGGAAGAGGAGACACGGAACACCAAGGCCCACGCACAGACUGACAGAAUGAACCUGCAGACCCUGCGCGGCUACUACAACCAGAGCGAGGCCAGUUCUCAUACCCUCCAGUGGAUGAUUGGCUGCGACCUGGGGUCCGACGGACGCCUCCUCCGCGGGUAUGAACAGUAUGCCUACGAUGGCAAGGAUUACCUCGCCCUGAACGAGGACCUGCGCUCCUGGACCGCAGCGGACACUGCGGCUCAGAUCUCCAAGCGCAAGUGUGAGGCGGCCAAUGUGGCUGAACAAAGGAGAGCCUACCUGGAGGGCACGUGCGUGGAGUGGCUCCACAGAUACCUGGAGAACGGGAAGGAGAUGCUGCAGCGCGCGGACCCCCCCAAGACACACGUGACCCACCACCCUGUCUUUGACUAUGAGGCCACCCUGAGGUGCUGGGCCCUGGGCUUCUACCCUGCGGAGAUCAUACUGACCUGGCAGCGGGAUGGGGAGGACCAGACCCAGGACGUGGAGCUCGUGGAGACCAGGCCUGCAGGGGAUGGAACCUUCCAGAAGUGGGCAGCUGUGGUGGUGCCUUCUGGAGAGGAGCAGAGAUACAUGUGCCAUGUGCAGCAUGAGGGGCUGCCGGAGCCCCUCAUGCUGAGAUGGAAGCAGUCUUCCCUGCCCACCAUCCCCAUCAUGGGUAUCGUUGCUGGUCUGGUUGUCCUUGCAGCUGUAGUCACUGGAGCUGCGGUCGCUGCUGUGCUGUGGAGGAAGAAGAGCUCAGAUUGAAAAGGAGGGAGCUACUCUCAGGCUGCAAUGUGAAACAGCUGCCCUGUGUGGGACUGAGUGGCAAGAUUUGUUCAUGCCUUCCCUUUGUGACUUCAAGAACCCUGACUUCUCUUUCUGCAGAGACCAGCCCACCCCUGUGCCCACCAUGACCCUCUUCCUCAUGCUGAACUGCAUUCCUUCCCCAAUCACCUUUCCUGUUCCAGAAAAGGGGCUGGGAUGUCUCCGUCUCUGUCUCAAAUUUGUGGUGCACUGAGCUAUAACUUACUUCUGUAUUAAAAUUAGAAUCUGAGUAUAAA